GUGUAAGGGGCUGGCGAGCAAGUGGGCAGCUGCUGAGCUUGCUGGGCCGGUGGGACGGAGCGGUCCAGGGACAGGCCCCUGCCUGGGCCAGAGAGGAGCCAGGAGCCAUGAGGGUGGCAUUAGGCAUGCUCUGGCUCUUGGCCCUUGCGUGGCCCCCCCAGGCCCGGGGCUUCUGCCCCUCUCAAUGCAGCUGCAGCCUCCAUAUCAUGGGUGAUGGCAGCAAGGCCAGGACAGUAGUGUGCAACGACCCCGACAUGACCCUGCCCCCGGCGUCCAUCCCCCCGGACACCUCCAGACUGCGCCUGGAGCGGACGGCCAUACGCAGGGUUCCUGGCGAGGCCUUCAGGCCCCUGGGCCGCCUGGAGCAGCUGUGGCUGCCUUACAACGCCCUCAGCGAGCUCAACGCCCUCAUGCUGCGGGGCCUGCGACGCCUGCGGGAGCUGCGGCUGCCCGGGAACCGCCUGGCCGCCUUCCCCUGGGCGGCGCUCAGGGACGCCCCCAAGCUGCGGCUGCUGGACCUGCAGGCCAACCGCCUCUCGGCUGUGCCCGCUGAGGCCGCGCGCUUCCUGGAGAACCUCACCUUCCUCGACCUCUCCAGCAACCAGCUGAUGAGGCUCCCGCAGGAGCUCAUCGUCUCCUGGGCUCACCUGGAGACCGGUAUCUUUCCUCCCGGCCACCACCCCAGGCGGGUCCUAGGGCUACAGGACAACCCCUGGGCAUGUGACUGCCGACUCUAUGACCUGGUUCAUCUUUUGGAUGGCUGGGCCCCAAACUUGGCCUUCAUUGAGACUGAACUGAGAUGUGCCAGCCCACGUAGCCUGGCCGGAGUGGCCUUCAGCCAGCUUGAACUGAGGAAGUGCCAGGGCCCAGAGCUCCAUCCAGGAGUGGCCAGCAUCAGGUCCCUUUUGGGUGGCACAGCACUGCUACGCUGUGGAGCUACUGGAGUCCCUGGGCCCGAGAUGAGCUGGAGGAGGGCCAAUGGCAGGCCCCUUAAUGGUACAGUGCACCAGGAAGUCUCCAGUGACGGCACGAGCUGGACUCUGCUGGGCCUGCCUGCAGUGUCCCACCUUGACUCCGGAGACUACAUCUGCCAAGCCAAGAACUUCCUGGGAGCCUCUGAAACUGUUAUCUCCUUGAUUGUCACUGAGCCACCGACUUCCACAGAACACAGUGGGAGCCCAGGAGCACUAUGGGCAAGGACAGGUGGCGGAGGGGAAGCUGCUGCUUACAACAACAAGCUGGUGGCCAGGCAUGUCCCCCAGAUUCCCAAACCCGCUGUCCUGGCCACUGGACCCUCUGUGCCCAGCACAAAGGAGGAGCUGACCCUUGAGCACUUCCAGAUGGAUGCCCUGGGAGAGCUCUCUGAUGGGCGGGCAGGACCCUCAGAGGCACGAAUGGUGAGGUCUGUGAAGGUGGUGGGGGACACUUACCACAGCGUGUCCUUGGUGUGGAAGGCACCCCAGGCUAAGAACACAACUGCCUUCAGUGUCCUCUACGCGGUCUUUGGGCAGCACAGCAUGCGGCGGGUGAUUGUGCAGCCUGGGAAGACCAGAGUGACCAUCACUGGGCUGUUGCCCAAGACCAAGUAUGUGGCGUGUGUCUGUGUGCAGGGCCUGGUGCCCCGGAAGGAGCAGUGUGUUAUUUUCUCCACCAAUGAAGUGGUGGAUGCUGAGAACACUCAGCAGCUUAUCAAUGUGGUGGUGAUCAGUGUGGCCAUCGUCAUUGCCCUGCCUCUCACGCUGCUUGUCUGCUGCAGUGCUCUUCAGAAGCGCUGCCGAAAGUGCUUCAACAAGGACUCCACUGAGGCCACAGUUACCUACGUCAACCUAGAGAGACUGGGCUACAGCGAGGACGGCUUGGAGGAGCUGUCCCGGCACAGUGUCAGCGAGGCUGACAGGCUUCUCUCAGCUCGUUCCAGUGUGGACUUUCAGGCCUUUGGAGUCAAAGGGGGCAGGAGAAUCAAUGAGUACUUCUGCUGAGGGAUAUGCCUCCGCAACUCACACACCUGCCUGCCCACGCUCCUUCUUUAGCUCUGACACCUGAGUACACGAUCACCCACUCUUACCUGCUCGGGUACCUGCUUACUCAGAUACUUACACACAACAACAGCAGCAGCAGCUGCUACUGCAACAACCGCUAACACUUGUUAAGCACUUACUACAGACUAGAAAGUGUUCUAAGUGCUAAAUUCUUGUAACAAUCAUUUGCAGCAGGCAUCACUAUUCUCUCCAUUUCCCUGGGGUGGGGGGUUAAGAAACUUGCCUGUAUCAGUCAGCUUUUGCUGUAUAACAAAUGAAAGCAAAAUCUUGGUGAUGUAUAGCAGUGAACACUUAUUUUCACACUCACAGGCCUGUGGGUUGAUUAGGGUGGCUCUGCUCUGUGUGUU